GCUCCCAGCACCCCUGGGGAGGGUCUCUCUCUCUCUCUCUCACACACACACACAUGCACACACGGCAGAGCAGGGCUGUGUGAGGCUGAGGACUGACAUUCUGGGCUCCAACUCUCUCUUCUGCUCAGUUUCCAGGGGUCCUGGGACAGGUGUCUUUGUCAGUUUUUGGCUCUGAGAAAUGAGGGAGUGGGGCAUGAACUUGACCUUGUUGAUGCUCUCUGUGUGGUAAAACCACGCAGAGAGGAACGUCAACAGAAGUGGGGGUUUCCAAGCCUGUAUGACACCAUCUGGGCAGGUCUGGGGUGCCCAGCCCUGGCAGAGAUGCCAGGAGCUGUGGCAGCACCCUCACCAGUCUGGUAGCUGGCCAGUUUCGAGGCCGCCAGCUACUGGGAGCACAUGCAGACCGGGCUCUCUGGCCUUUAAUUCUUGUGAUUCUGUUCCUUGCAGGCUUUGAGCUGCUUGGAGCAGGGGCUGGAGCAGCCAUGACCCGCUGGAAGUCCCUCAAGGCCCCUGGGCCACACAAAUCCAGCCCCUGUCAGCUGGUGGCCUCACGCCGGCGUCUGAGUGCCCCGGCCCUGGCUGCCUCCUUCUGGAGGGUCCAGGAAUCUGGGGCUGAGCCCCUUUCCCAGCACAGCCUCAGGGGUCCCCCCUGCCGCCAGCUCCCUACUUCCAGGCCCAGGCAGAAGCAGUGUCCACCAUUCCGGCCCUGCGUCCCAGCUCCUCAGCGUCAUGGAGCCGCCCUGCCUGGAGCUAGCCUGGGGGUGAGCCAGGGUCCCCCAACCCCCGGGAUGACCGCGGCCAGCCGGGCCAACCCCUACAGCAUCGUGUCAUUGGAGGAGGACGGGCUGCACCUGGUCACCAUGUCGGGCGCCAACGGCUUCGGCAACGGCAAGGUGCACACGCGGCGCAGGUGCCGCAACCGCUUCGUCAAGAAGAAUGGCCAGUGCAACAUUGCGUUCGCCAACAUGGACGAGAAGUCACAGCGCUACCUGGCUGACAUGUUCACCACCUGUGUGGACAUCCGCUGGCGCUACAUGCUGCUCAUCUUCUCGCUGGCCUUCCUUGCCUCCUGGCUGCUGUUCGGCGUCAUCUUCUGGGUCAUCGCGGUGGCACACGGUGACCUGGAGCCGGCUGAGGGCCACGGCCGCACACCCUGUGUGAUGCAGGUGCACGGCUUCAUGGCGGCCUUCCUCUUCUCCAUCGAGACGCAGACCACCAUCGGCUACGGGCUGCGCUGUGUGACGGAGGAGUGCCUGGUGGCCGUCUUCAUGGUGGUGGCCCAGUCCAUCGUGGGCUGCAUCAUCGACUCCUUCAUGAUUGGUGCCAUCAUGGCCAAGAUGGCAAGGCCCAAGAAGCGGGCACAGACGCUGCUGUUCAGCCACAACGCCGUGGUGGCCCUGCGUGACGGCAAGCUCUGCCUCAUGUGGCGUGUGGGCAACCUGCGCAAGAGCCACAUUGUGGAGGCCCAUGUGCGCGCGCAGCUCAUCAAGCCGCGGGUCACCGAGGAGGGCGAGUACAUCCCGCUGGACCAGAUCGACAUCGAUGUGGGCUUCGACAAGGGCCUGGACCGCAUCUUUCUGGUGUCGCCCAUCACCAUCUUGCAUGAAAUUGACGAGGCCAGCCCGCUCUUCGGCAUCAGCCGGCAGGACCUGGAGACGGACGACUUUGAGAUCGUGGUCAUCCUGGAAGGCAUGGUGGAGGCCACAGCCAUGACCACCCAGGCCCGCAGCUCCUACCUGGCCAAUGAGAUCCUGUGGGGUCACCGCUUUGAGCCCGUGCUCUUCGAGGAGAAGAACCAGUACAAGAUUGACUACUCGCACUUCCACAAGACCUAUGAGGUGCCCUCUACGCCCCGCUGCAGUGCGAAGGAUCUGGUAGAGAACAAGUUCCUGCUGCCCAGUGCCAACUCCUUCUGCUAUGAGAACGAGCUGGCCUUCCUGAGCCGUGACGAGGAGGAUGAGGCGGACGGAGACCAGGACGGCCGAAGCCGGGAUGGCCUCAGCCCCCAGGCCAGGCAUGACUUUGACAGACUCCAGGCUGGCGGCGGGGUCCUGGAGCAGCGGCCCUACAGACGGGGGUCAGAGAUCUGAGCCAACCUUGGCCGACAUGCAGCAUCCACCCCUGGCCGGGGAGAGGCCCCGCGGUCGCUCAGGGGCCCUGGGUUUGAGCAGAACGGGCCCAGUGCCCUGGGUUGCAGACUCAGUAGCGUUUUAGUCGUUUUAUGUUUCUUUGCAAAGGCCUCAGAAGGUUGGCCGGAGAGGGGGCAGCCAGAGCGGCAGCCCCCGGCCUCAGAGGCUAUCACAGGCUCAGGGCAAAGAAGUGGCCUCCUGGGGGGCCAGGCCACGGGGGCCAGGGCUUCUGCCUGAAGAUGGAGCUGCAGCCUGCGGGGAAGCAGCCCAGCUCGAUGGUGGGCCCAGCCUCUGCUGUCCAAGGCUGGCUAGCUGCGGUGCUCCUUGCUGGUUUUUAACUUGGGGAGAAACACCGGGUUUCAGCUUUCUCGACCUUAGCUUGGGUGAGACUGUUUACAAAAAAAAAAAAAACCAUGCAAUUGGAGAAAAAAAUUUUAAUUCAUAGGGGGCAAAAAGAACAAUUAGAAUUCCAUGGGUCUGCCAGG